AUACUUGGCCUCACACACCCAUCUGCUCACUCACCCUGGCACAUUCAGCCCCCCUAACCCACCUUGAACAUUGACCACCACACACUCCCUGGCACGCUCUUCUCACCCUCAACUUCUGCCACCUCUCCCUGGGCAAUACUGCCAGCCUUUCCCUAAUCUCAGAGCUGCAGCCCUGCCCUGUCACUCACCUCAAACCUGCCAUGUCCCUGGGGCUACUGAAAUUCCAGGCAGUGGGUGAAGAGGACGAGGAGGAUGAGGAGGGGGAGAGCCUGGACUCUGUGAAGGCACUGACAGCCAAGCUGCAGCUGCAGACUCGGCGGCCCUCAUAUCUGGAGUGGACAGCCCAGGUCCAGAGCCAGGCCUGGCGCAGGGCCCAAGCCAAACCUGGACCAGGGGGACCUGGGGACAUCUGUGGUUUCGACUCAAUGGACUCCGCCCUUGAGUGGCUCCGACGGGAGCUGCGGGAGAUGCAGGCGCAGGACAGGCAGCUGGCAGGGCAGCUGCUGCGGCUGCGGGCCCAGCUGCACCGACUGAAGAUGGACCAAGCCUGUCACCUGCACCAGGAGCUGCUGGAUGAGGCCGAGCUGGAGCUGGAGCUGGAGCCCGGGGCCGGCCUAGCCCUGGCCCCGCUGCUGCGGCACCUGGGCCUCACGCGCAUGAACAUCAGCGCCCGGCGCUUCACCCUCUGCUGAGGAACACCUGUGCCCCCCGACUCCCCGCCCCCUCUCCCAAUGCCGCUUCCCCUGCCUGCCUGGGAAGAGGAAAGGGAGGGGUGCCCCAGAGGCACCAGCUCCUGGCGGGGGAGGAGGAACAUUCAGGUUUCUGAGAGCUGAAUUCCAAGAGUGCAAAACCCCAGCAUCCUGUUUCCUCUGCUGACCCAGCUGGGAGGGGGAGGAGGAGGAGCUCACACCCUCAAACUCCUCAAUAAACGCUUUCUCUGGUUCCCA